AAGCCUUCCAAACCCUCCUUCCUGGAAACCCACCCAGAACCUCCACCCUCUGACACCAUGGUCAACUCCUGUUGUGGCUCUGUGUGCUCUGACCAGGGCUGUGGCCUAGAGAACUGCUGCCGUCCCAGCUACUGCCAGACCACCUGCUGCAGGACCACCUGCUGCCGCCCCAGCUGCUGUGUGUCCAGCUGCUGCAGACCCCAGUGCUGCCAGACCACCUGCUGCAGGACCACCUGCUGCCACCCCAGCUGCUGUGUGUCCAGCUGCUGCAGACCCCAGUGCUGCCAGUCUGUGUGCUGCCAGCCCACCUGCUGCAGACCCCAAUGCUGCCAGACUACCUGCUGUAGGACCACCUGCUGCCGCCCCAGCUGCUGCAGGCCCCAGUGCUGCCAGUCUGUGUGCUGCCAGCCCACCUGCUGCUGCCCCAGCUACUGUGUGUCCAGCUGCUGCAGACCCCAGUGCUGCCAGACCACCUGCUGCAGAACCACCUGCUGCCGCCCCAGCUGCUGUGUGUCCAGGUGCUACAGGCCCCAUUGUGGCCAGUCUCUAUGCUGCUAGCCCAUCUGCUGGCAAACCACCUGCUACAGGACCACCUGCUGCCACCCCAGCUAUUGCAUUUCCAGCUGCUGCCAGCCUUCCUGCAGUAUCUCUAGCAGCAGUAGCUCCUCCUGCUGUGGCUUCAGCUGCUGCAGGCUCUCCUGCUGCAUCUCCAGUUGCUGCCGCCCCAACUGCUGCCAGACCAUGUGCUGCCGCCCAACCUGCUCUAGUGCUUCUUGCUGCUGAGGCUGUCAUCUGGACUCACCAGAUUCUCAUCAACCAGCAUUCUUGAUGUAGCUCAUCUAUGAGCUGAGUUAUGGGAAGCUAGUUGGAAAACUUCAGUUCCAACCAAUUCUUAGAUUGAAUCUGGCCUCCAAAUAUAUGCUCCCCCCACAUUUUACCUCUCUACCAAAUGAACAUAAGUUGUAAUUUGCUCUGAAAUCUGUCAACUAUCUUAAUUGAAAUAUUUGCUCUCUGCCAUAAUUUCUCAUAUGGAGCUAUUCCAUUUUAAACAAAUAUUUAUCUAAAUAAAUCUUAAAUAAAUUUUCAGGCAUAGAAAUAUA